AGCACAGAGUUGGGAGUGACUCCAGAGCCUCCAGCGAGAUGCUGCUGAUUCUGCUGUCAGUGGCCCUGCUGGCCCUGAGCUCAGCUGAGAGUUCAAGUGAAGAUGUCAGCCAGGAAGAAUCUCUCUUCCUAAUAUCAGGAAAGCCAGAAGGACGACGCCCACAAGGAGGAAACCAGCCCCAACGUCCCCCACCUCCUCCAGGAAAGCCACAAGGACCACCCCCACAAGGAGGAAACCAGUCCCAAGGUCCCCCACCUCCUCCAGGAAAGCCAGAAGGACGACCCCCACAAGGAGGCAACCAGUCCCAAGGUCCCCCACCUCAUCCAGGAAAGCCAGAAAGACCACCCCCACAAGGAGGAAACCAGUCCCAAGGUACCCCACCUCCUCCAGGAAAGCCAGAAAGACCACCCCCACAAGGAGGCAACCAGUCCCACCGUCCCCCACCUCCUCCAGGAAAGCCAGAAAGACCACCCCCACAAGGAGGUAACCAGUCCCAAGGUCCCCCACCUCAUCCAGGAAAGCCAGAAGGACCACCCCCACAGGAAGGAAACAAGUCCCGAAGUGCCCGAUCUCCUCCAGGAAAGCCACAAGGACCACCCCAACAAGAAGGCAACAAGCCUCAAGGUCCCCCACCUCCUGGAAAGCCACAAGGCCCACCCCCAGCAGGAGGCAAUCCCCAGCAGCCUCAGGCACCUCCUGCUGGAAAGCCCCAGGGGCCACCUCCACCUCCUCAAGGGGGCAGGCCACCCAGACCUGCCCAGGGACAACAGCCUCCCCAGUAAUCUAGGAUUCAAUGACAGGAAGUGAAUAAGAAGAUAUCAGUGAAUUCAAAUAAUUCAAUUGCUACAAAUGCCGUGACAUUGGAACAAGGUCAUCAUAGCUCUAACUUUAAUAUACCAAUAAAAUAAUCAGCUUGCAAUUUC